UUGAGAGCGUGGUCUUGGAGGCAGCUGACCAUCUGACCACCUGAACCUCAGUUUCCCCUCCUGUAAAGGAGGAUGGGACGGCGCCUACCUCCUGGGCUGUUGUGGGGAUUGAAUCAGCAUGCCGCACACCGGCUGUGGAAUAGACAGUGGGAGUCAUUUUAAAAAGGGGUCUUUCAGUCCUUGGGGAGUUGUCUUUUCUCUUCUUUGUAUACAAAGAGCUUCAGGCUGUCACCAGGCUGGACUCGAGGUGUACCUGAAGUGGAAGCACUGCGAGACGCCAGGCGUGAAGACCCUGUGUAAUCUGAAGCACUGCGAGACGCCAGGAGUGAAGACCCUGUGUAAUCUGAAGAAACUUCUGAAUCGGCUUCAGAAAGACCACCGGGAGGACGUCUACCUCUACAUCUCUGGACACCUGAACCCCAACAAGCUCUACCAGCCUCCGGAGACGAUCUUACAGCACUGGCCCAAUGCCCACCGGCCCAAGGGGGAGCGCGCCUCUGAGGUGGGAGAGCCGCCCGCAGGGAAGGUGGCGAGGAUGAAGGAGGCCCUGGCCCACUUCACCAUCCACACGGCCCUGGUCCCCAGUGAGGCCCAGGACACCCCGCUGUUCAGGUACCUGAACCCCCAGGCCUCUCUUUCCCACACUUCAGAGGAGGAUUUCCUUCCAGUGGAGGCUGUCAGAGAGGGGAAGGAAGAAAAGAAAGGAGGCCCUCCUGGACGGGGCCCUCCUGGAUGGCGCAGGAGGGAAGAACUCCGGCUGCCCGACUUGAAGGUGCUGUGCUACCAGGAGGCCGGGUCCAGAGGCACCAGGGACCGGCACCACUAUGUCAGCUCCUACCUGGCCGGAGCCACCAGCGCAGACAGGUACAGGAUGUUCCUGCGUUUCCAGAAGGAAGUGCUCGCCAAGCAAGAUCUCCUGAAGAAUGACUUCACUGGGAGCAAGGCGGCCGCGGGCCACGAGAGAAAGCUGCAGCAGGAGCUCCAGAAAAUUUGCACGUGCAGCCCCCAGCAGUUCAACAGACUGCACGUCUUUGGAAAAGUCUUUGAAGAUAUUUGUAACAGUUCUUUGAUAUUUGGUGAUCUCUUGAAAAAAGUUAAGGAUGAAUAUGAACUCUACAUGGCAACGCUCCUGGAGUCCCAGCCUGCAGCACAGUACGAGGCUCUUCUGGCUCAACUCAAGGCGCUGGGGCAGAGGCCGGUGAAGACGGCGGACAUGGAUCUCGCCAGGGAAGAGCUGAGGAUGCUCGUGACAGCCACAAAAGCAGCCCUGGAGCAGAAUGAUAGACUCAGAAGUGAACUGGAGAUGGAGGUGGCAUUGCUGCAGUCUGCAAAGGAACGAUCAGAAUCAUCUGAGAAACAUAUAAUUGAUGAAAACCGACUUACUCUUACUGAGAAGGUUGAAAAGAAGAGGUGUGAAAUACUCAGUAAGUGGGAUGAGAUACAAGCUCUGGAAAAAGAAAUUAAAACAACUUUGGUUCAUACUGGAAUUUCAGAUAUCACUGAGAAUAGGAUUAAAAGCAUAGAGCAUGAAGCUAUACAAUUGGAAACAGAAAAUAUGAUUUUAAAGAAGAAAAUAAAAGUUACUGAAAACCAUGUGAAGCAGAUCAUAGGAAAGAUCAGUGAAGAGAGGCAGGAGGGCCUUUGGAAAUUUAUCAAGGAAUUUGUAAAAUCAGAGGAAACAGAAGAUAACGCUCAAGUGGCUGAACAAAUGGCCAGUGGAAAUUCUUAACUUCCAUGUAUGUAGCAUGGAUAUUUGCAGAUGCAUAUACAUUCAUAAAGAUACAUUUCAUUUCAUCAGCUUUAAUCUCUAGUAAAAUUAAUGUGGUAUAUGUAUCCUACUCAGGAUACUGAAAUACACACAUGCGUACACAUGAUUAGUUUCUGUUGCAUACAUAUUUACAACAAUACUAGUUCUUAACGUAUGUUUUACUUUCAUUUAAUAAUGUUCAACUUUGGAAAAUACUUUUGAUUAUUUGCUAAGAAUAAGGAAUUCAGCGCUGCUUGAAUACAGCUCAAAUUUGUUUAUUUGCCAACACAAGUUUACAUAUAUGCAUUUAAUAAAAUUUUAUAGUGAUUUAAUAA